UAUAUAUAUACACAUAUAUACGUAUAUAUGUGUAUAUAUAUACACAUAUAUACGUAUAUAUGUGUAUAUACACAUAUAUACAUAUAUGUGUAUAUAUGUACACAUAUAUGUGUGUAUAUAUGUACACAUAUAUGUGUGUAUAUAUGUACACAUAUAUGUGUGUAUAUAUGUAUACAUAUAUGUGUGUAUAUGUAUACAUAUAUGUGUGUAUAUGUAUACAUAUAUGUGUGUAUAUAUGUAUACAUAUAUAUGUGUAUAUAUGUAUACAUAUAUGUGUAUAUAUGUAUACAUAUAUGUGUAUAUAUGUAUACAUAUAUAUGUGUACAUAUAUAUGUGUAUAUAUGUGUACAUAUAUAUGUGUAUAUAUGUGUGUAUAUAUGUGUACAUAUAUAUGUGUAUAUAUGUAUACAUAUAUAUGUGUAUAUAUGUAUACAUAUAUAUAUAUGUGUAUAUGUGUAUACAUAUAUAUGUGUAUAUGUGUAUACAUAUAUAUGUGUAUAUGUGUAUACAUAUAUAUGUGUAUAUGUGUAUACAUAUAUAUGUGUAUAUGUGUAUACAUAUAUAUGUGUAUAUGUGUAUACAUAUAUACGUAUAUGUAUACAUAUAUGUAUACAUAUAUAUGUGUAUAUAUGUAUAUAUGUGUAUAUAUAUACAUAUAUAUACAUAUAUUUACUUAUCAAGAUUUAUGAGCUUUUUACUCCUUACGUGAACUUUAUACCUCUCUUCACAAAUCAAUUGUAUGAAGAACAGGAUUCACUGCAACCUGCCUAA